ACUCGCCUGGAGCGCGCGGGCAAGGCGGGCGGAGCGCACUGGAACUCAAGGGGGCGCACAGCGGCGCGCUCGCACCGCUCGGCUCCGCGCGGCUCUAGGAGGUGGCGGCGGUGGCGGUGGCGGCGGUGGCGGCGGCGGCGGCGGCGGGGCGCAGGGCUGAGCGAGCGUCCGGGUUCCGGGGCUCCGGGGAAGGCGGUUGCAGCUCCUGAGUGCAGCGCGGCUUCCUGCCACUGUCCCGGCCCGGCCACCUCUCUGUCAUGGCUCUGGCGGACAGCACACGUGGAUUACCCAACGGGGGCGGCGGCGGGGGCGGCAGUGGCUCCUCGUCGUCCUCCGCGGAGCCACCGCUCUUCCCCGACAUCGUGGAGCUGAACGUGGGGGGCCAGGUGUACGUGACCCGGCGCUGCACGGUGGUGUCGGUGCCCGACUCGCUGCUCUGGCGCAUGUUCACGCAGCAGCAGCCGCAGGAGCUGGCCCGGGACAGCAAAGGCCGCUUCUUUCUGGACCGGGACGGCUUCCUCUUCCGCUACAUCCUGGAUUACCUGCGGGACUUGCAGCUCGUGCUGCCCGACUACUUCCCCGAGCGCAGCCGGCUGCAGCGCGAGGCCGAGUACUUCGAGCUGCCAGAGCUCGUGCGCCGCCUCGGGGCGCCCCAGCAGCCCGGCCCGGGGCCGCCGCCCUCGCGGCGCGGGGUGCACAAGGAGGGCUCGCUGGGUGACGAGCUGCUGCCGCUUGGCUACUCGGAGCCCGAACAGCAGGAGGGCGCCUCUGCCGGGGCGCCGUCGCCCACGCUGGAGCUGGCUAGCCGCAGUCCGUCCGGGGGCGCGGCGGGCCCGCUGCUCACGCCGUCCCAGUCGCUGGACGGCAGCCGGCGCUCGGGCUACAUCACCAUCGGCUACCGCGGCUCCUACACCAUCGGGCGGGACGCGCAGGCGGACGCCAAGUUCCGGCGAGUGGCGCGCAUCACCGUUUGCGGAAAGACGUCGCUGGCCAAGGAGGUGUUUGGGGACACCCUGAACGAAAGCCGGGACCCCGACCGUCCCCCGGAGCGCUACACCUCGCGCUAUUACCUCAAGUUCAACUUCCUGGAGCAGGCCUUCGACAAGCUGUCCGAGUCGGGCUUCCACAUGGUGGCGUGCAGCUCCACGGGCACCUGCGCCUUUGCCAGCAGCACCGACCAGAGCGAGGACAAGAUCUGGACCAGCUACACCGAGUACGUCUUCUGCAGGGAGUGAGCUCCCCAGACCCCCUCGCCACUCCAGCGCCCAGUCCUUCUCCUGCCCGAGAGAUGAUUACAGAGCCUCUUGUCCCACCUUUGUCCCCUGGCUGCUGCCCUCCCAUUCUCCCCCUCCAGUAGUAGCUGGGUGAGACCUGUCCGCCCACCUUCCCUCCACUACAGAACCUGCAGCCGCAAAUCCUCUGGGCUGCUUCGUCUUCUUUGGACCUCCUGAACCGAGAGAACCCAGAGGAACCCCCACCCCACCCCCACCUACCACUCCAUGCUUUCUCUACUCCCUGCCUCAAACCACCCCUCCCCCAGAUGGUACUUCAGUUUGGAUCUAUUGGGGGAGUGUGGCCACAGACCGGGGGAUGAUUGAAUUGUUCAGAACCUGAUUGGACCGUGUCCAAUGUGCGGAAGAUUUCCUUGAAAUCUUCUCAAGCUCUUAUGACUCACUGGGGGUUUAAGAGAUCAGGAUUGGUUCCACUGUCUGGGGUUAGUGUUUUACAAGGUCAUUACACAGUCUUUUUGACCUCUUUUGAAGGUAGAGUUUUAGAAGGCUGGAUGGAAGAUUCUGAGCCUGGAAUUAGGACCCCAUGGAGGCAGUUCAGUAACUAAACUAAUAAAGUUUUGAAAAGUUACACGUAAAGUAGAAGAAUCUAGUGCGUGGGACAGUAAAGGAUCCUUUCUCGUACAGAAUAAAAGGUCUCAGCCUGUAGCUUAAACUUAUAGAAAGUGAUCCGCCUGCCUGCAGAGGCGCCCUUUUCAGCUGCUGCUCGCCAGAAGCCCUUGAUUCCACUGGUUGACAUGGCAGCAGUUACUGGCAAGAGGGAGAAAGGACGCUGCCGCCUAAGAGUGCAAGGCUGCUCAGGUCUCCAAGCGCCGUAGGAGGUCACCUGGCAGUGACUGUAGGGAGCUGGGUCAUAGUGCACGUCGUGGGUAUUAGGAAAGCCUGUAUUCUUUCAAUGAAUGUCAGUAGGACCUUCCUUUAGCUGUAAGACUUGGUGGGCGGGGUGGGGUGGGGAGGGAGGAAAGGGUAGGAAGGGUGGGAAGGGAGAAGCAGACAUAGUCAUUUAUGAUUUGAAAGUUGGAAGUUUGUACCAUCUGUUUGAGUAUAUGCACAUUUAAAAAAUAUCAUAUAGUAAAUGCAAACAUGCCAAGUAUUUUAUAAAGAUUAAUAACAGACCUACUCUUACCUGGCAGUUUACUUAACUUACUGUUUUGAGUCCUAAACUUAGAGUUGUUAAUGCUUAUAUAUAAUCUAACCAAAGAGUUACCCAGUAGGGUUUUAGUUUUUGAACUUUUAUUUUCUUGUUGAUUAUAAAUCCUGAUUUUGGAAUCUAUUGCGCAAAAGAAGUUUCAUUUUGGUUACUUAGACCUAAGAUCACUUAUUAAAAAUCCUUAUUUUCUCCAAGCCCAGCAAACGUUGACUUCUGGGCAAACCUGAAAACCUGAAAAUGCCACUUUCAUGCAGUUUGUUUGAAGUUAAGUGGAAUCCUUUCAAAUGACGAGCUGCAGAGAACUCAGCACCAAGGGCUGCCUAUCUGUAGAUAGCUGUAAAAUGGAAUAUUUUUAAAUGAAGGCAAAUAAGUACUUAAAAGUGAGCUGAGCAAUAAAAUGGUCCAAUAAUAGGUAAAUGCAACAGAAACAGAAGGAGACCUGGUUGCCUUAUGCCUUUACUCUUACAUGGAAUAAAUUCCCAAUGCAUAUCCUAUGUAAACCAUAAGUGAAGGGAAAUAAACCUCGUCAUGCUCCAUGCUGUGAGGUGUCCUUUGGAUAUUCUGUGAUGACAGAGAAGCCUAUUUUGUUUUGUUUUCAGCAUCUUUCUCUGAUGUACGUUUUUAAGGAUUUUGUAAGAGCUGUUUUCAGUGUUUAAAUUAGUGCUAUUUUUCCUUGUUUUUAAAAAUGAAUCUCGUACUGUAUCUUACUAUGUCCAUACAGAUGUUACAAAUCGACAGUUUUAUUCUUAGACUCAUGUGAUCCAAGCUGUAUAUACCAUAUAUAAACAUUUUACAUGAAUCAUUUAGUUUUUUAAUUCAUUUACUAAUGCUAUAAAAUUUCCUAUAUUACCCCAGUAAUUUGCAUCAGCUGGUUUAUAUACUAAAGCAACAUGUUUUGAUGAGUUUCUUACAUCCUUAUCGAGGAAUUGGGUUAGGAAAAAAUACAUAAUUGUAAAACUGAGUUUGCUGUAUUAUACUUUUUUUCUUGAGUAUUAGUUGUAUUACUAAUCAUAUGUUGAUUAACUGUCUACUUAAAGUCAAGGUACCUGUAUUUUUAAUCCACUAAUUUUUUUUUAGUUGGGAAAUAGAUUUCAGGUCUUUUAUUAGACUAACAUUUUUUGAGAAGUAAAAUUGACUUCAUAUACAAAGCCUGUAAUUUUAGGCGAAAUGGAAGCAGAAAUCUAGGAAGUUGUGCUUGCUUGUAUGUUGAGUUUGGUCUCAGACUAAGUAAUGCAUCAGAAUUCAUCUGUUUGAAGCCUGAAAUAAUUUAGGACUCUGAUUCACUGACCAAAAGUCAGUGUUGCAGAGAUUUCUCUACCCCGUAUGGUAUUUUGUUAGAUUGUUCAACAGGAAGCACAUGAUUGAGAACAUCUUGGGACAGACCAAAACCACUGACAGAUGGCAAGGCUCGGCGAUUCUGAUUUCCCUUCUCAAAUCUGCUCAACUCCAAGAGUCUUGAGAAACUGCUAAAAUUUUGCCUCUGUCACUCAAGUCUUACAAAUGUUAUCUUGUAAACCUUUGAGGUGAACUAUUCCACUGUCUUGUACAUAGGCAUCUUAUUCACUGCACCCUGUCACACCCAGCACCCCCCGCCCCGCACAUUAUUUGAAAGACUGGGAAUUUAAUGGUUAGGGACAGUAAAUCUACUUCUUUUUCCAGGGACGACUGUCCCCUCUAAAGUUAAAGUCAAUACAAGAAAACUGUCUAUUUUUAGCCUAAAGUAAAGGCUGUGAAGAAAAUUCAUUUUACAUUGGGUAGACAGUAAAAAACAAGUAAAAUAACUUGACAUGAGCACCUUUAGAUCCCUUCCCCUCCAUGGGCUUUGGGCCACAGAAUGAACCUUUGAGGCCUGUAAAGUGGAUUGUAAUUUCCUAUAAGCUGUAAUAGUGGAGGUAUUGUGGGUUCAUUUGAGUAAGCCCUCCAAAGAUACCAUUCAAAUAACCUGGGAGAAUGUCAUAAAUUAUUCAGAUAAUUAACACUGCAUGAAUCUGAUUCAGAGGCAUGCAUUUACAUAUGUUGCCCUAAUUACCAUUUGAUGAUCAUAAAUACAAGUGAAUGACAUUGGACUUUUAGUAACAAACUUAAUUUUUAAAAAGGUGUAGACAAUGGUGGUUAAAAAAAAAAAAAAAACAGGUACCAGGUUCUGUGUGUUUGCACCAAGUAAUUGACAUGUUUUUUAAUACAUGUGGACCAUGAACAGUAUUCAUUCUACUUUUUCAAAUGAUAUGCUGUAGAAAAUAUUCCUUGAAGAUGUGAGAUUUAAAAAUUUUUCCCUUUCAAUGUUGUUAUGUAUUCUACUGGUUUUUGAUUGAUAGCACAGUGAUAAAUCAUAAUACUAGACAAAAUUGUCUUCUCUUUCAAACCAGAGCCAUAUAUAUGUCUGUAUAUAUGGGACCUACUGCUUCUCUGAGGAAAUGCAUAAUCUGUUAAUAUCAGACAAAAUGAGCAAUUGGCAGUGCUCAUAAUAUAUUCCAAUUUUUAUUGGAAUUUUCGAUGGAAUGUUAUUUCAAUAAAGCCAUGUAAGGUGAAACUUUGAUAACUUUUUACUCUUCAAGUUAGGGUAAAUUCUGAUCCAAUAUUCAAUUCAUUUGUGUACUCCCACAUGCAAAAUGCUAAAUUACAAUGCAGACAUUAAGAAAAAGUAUUGACUGGAGGGGUUGAAUUCCUUGAGAAUUUAUUUUAUAGUCUAAAUCACAAAUACUUUACUCAAUUUAGUUUUUAAAAUAGUAAACUGAAUAUUUUUGUUGUAAGCCUAUCAGAGUCAAUCCUUCGUUUGGAAUUGUUUUCCUGUUUUUCCUUACUAUAAAUCAUUUAAAAACUGAAUUCAUUUUCUUAGAUGGCAUAAGUCUGUCUCUUGAGAAAUAAGUAAAAUACUCCUAUUUUCAGUAUCUGUAGCACCUGAAAUAGGUCUUUGUAUAGCCAGAAACAAGUUAUGUUGAAGUUAGCUUUUCUUUGUCAACAGUUUUGGACAAUAAAAAUCUGAAAGUAUUAACACUUGAUUUUCUACUGGGGCCCUUCAAACUUGGUUGGAAGAAAUUCAACCAGAAUAUCUACAUUAGAGUAUAAUCAUGUGUGGUAGGAAGAUGGACUAGUUAAUCAAGAUUUGUUGUCACUUAAAUUUUUUGUGAUUUUUUUCCAAGCCAGUUUUUUUAAAUUCUAAAUGUGUUUUGAGGUAUGGGUACAUUAAUUGUAAUGUAAACUAUUAUACAACUGUUUUUGCGACUUUAUAGGCAGGUAAAUUUUGCUAUUACUAUUGAAUACAAAUGACAAUUCAUUUAUGACCACUCAAACAGCGUUAGUAACCAUUUAGUGACAAAGGAUUAAAACAUCCAUCUGGAUGUUAAUUUUGAAGAUGUAAAUUAUAUGUUGUUUAAAUUUUUCCAGGCAUCUGAAAACCUUAUCUGCUAGACAAUGUAAGAUUCACACAGAGUUAUCUGGGAUUCUGAUUUUUUAAAUAGUACAUAUCAUUAAACCAUUUUCUCUAAAUGUAAGAAGAGCAGAAAAAAUCUUAUAAGAUUAUCAGAUUUUUCUAAUGACACAGAAAUGUAAGAAAAAAAUCCCUUUAUAUUGAAAAAAGAUGCAGUCAAAGUCUUUUCAGACAUGCCCAAACUUUGAGAAUUUCUUCAACCAUCUAAUGCUAUAAAGAUUUUUGUUCUUCCUGUUCACAACCAGUUGUAUAACAGAAAUACUAGCUACUGUUUUCCUUCCUGUGUGUGAAGUAAUGAAUCAUUGAUUAUGUGACUUGUUAUGUAUUCAAUUAAACACUAAAGAAUAAAACAUUCACUCCUUUAA